GUUUGGCCUUUUCGGAUGCUGUGUCUGCCAGGCCAACUCUGUCUCCCUACUUGUUGAUGGUGGGCAGAAAGUCUCACUAAUUCAUAAAUUCUUGGCCAGAGUGUGCCCAUCAACAGGGGUUACACUUGCCACCUCCUUAAAUCCCAGCUCAAUGCAUUCUCCAUGCUCCUGGCUAUUCAGGUGGGGUUUACCUGAAGGCAUGUACCUGGAAUAGUUGACCUCUGACAAAUUCCAAAUGUCUCUGAAGACAUUGUCAAAAGGGACACCCUCAAGAAAAUGGUUUCAGAAAUGCCGACAUUCAUUUGCUUUUCUAGUCAAGCCUCAACUGUUUGCCGGAGAACUGGAGAAGUUAAAUCAGUCCACGGAUGAUAUCAACAGACGGGAGACUGAACUUGAGGAUGCUCGUCAGAAGUUCCGCUCUGUUCUGGUUGAAGCAACGGUGAAACUGGAUGAACUGGUGAAGAAAAUUGGCAAAGCUGUGGAAGACUCCAAGCCCUACUGGGAGGCACGGAGGGUGGCGAGGCAGGCUCAGCUGGAAGCUCAGAAAGCCACGCAGGACUUCCAGAGGGCCACAGAGGUGCUCCGUGCCGCCAAGGAGACCAUCUCCCUGGCCGAGCAGCGGCUGCUGGAGGAUGACAAGCGGCAGUUCGACUCCGCCUGGCAGGAGAUGCUGAAUCACGCCACUCAGAGGGUCAUGGAGGCGGAGCAGACCAAGACCAGGAGCGAGCUGGUGCAUAAGGAGACGGCAGCCAGGUACAAUGCCGCCAUGGGCCGCAUGCGACAGCUGGAGAAGAAACUCAAGAGAGCCAUCAACAAGUCCAAGCCUUAUUUUGAACUCAAGGCAAAGUACUAUGUGCAGCUCGAGCAACUGAAAAAGACUGUGGAUGACCUGCAGGCCAAACUGACCCUGGCAAAAGGCGAGUACAAGAUGGCCCUGAAGAACCUGGAGAUGAUCUCAGAUGAGAUCCACGAGCGGCGGCGCUCCAGUGCCAUGGGGCCUCGGGGAUGCGGUGUUGGUGCUGAGGGCAGCAGCACAUCUGUGGAGGAUCUGCCAGGGAGCAAACCUGAGCCUGAUGCCAUUUCUGUGGCCUCGGAGGCCUUUGAAGAUGACAGCUGUAGCAACUUUGUGUCUGAAGAUGACUCGGAAACCCAGUCCGUGUCCAGCUUUAGUUCAGGACCAACAAGCCCGUCUGAGAUGCCUGACCAGUUCCCUGCGGUUGUGAGGCCUGGCAGCCUGGAUCUGCCCAGCCCUGUGUCCCUGUCAGAGUUUGGGAUGAUGUUCCCAGUGUUGGGCCCUCGAAGUGAAUGCAGCGGGGCCUCCUCCCCUGAAUGUGAAGUAGAACGAGGAGACAGGGCAGAAGGGGCAGAGAAUAAAACAAGUGACAAAGCCAACAACAACCGGGGCCUCAGCAGUAGCAGUGGCAGUGGUGGCAGCAGUAAGAGCCAAAGCAGCACCUCCCCUGAGGGCCAGGCCUUGGAGAACCGGAUGAAGCAGCUCUCCCUACAGUGCUCAAAGGGAAGAGAUGGAAUUAUUGCUGACAUAAAAAUGGUGCAGAUUGGCUGAUUCAUCCUGGGCCCUGGCCGAUGUGCAUAUCAACAUUUAUACAUGGAACUGGAGAACAUUGUGCCAAUAAUCAUUUAAUAUAUGCCAAAUCUUACACGUCUACUCUAAACUGCUCUAAUGAAGUUUCAGUGACCUUGAGGGCUAAAGAUUGUUCUUCUGGGUAAGAGCUCUUGGGCUGGUUUUUCAGAGCAGAGUUCUUGUUGUGGGUAGACUGUGACUAGGUUCACAGCCUUUGUGGAACAUUCCGUAUAACGGCAUUGUGGAAGCAAUAACUAGUUCCUAUGAAAGAACCAGAGCUGGGAAGAUGGCUGGGAAGCCAGGCCAAAGUGGGGGCAACAGCUUGCUUCUCUUUCUCUUCUCACCCUCAGUUUGUAUGGGAAAAUGGAGAUGUCCUCUCCACUUUAUCCCACGAUAUCUAAAUGAAAAAGAAAGAAAACCCACACACAAAGCAAAAACUCAAGUAUUAAGAGCACAUAUUUUUGACCCAGUGGAGGCUUAAAAAAAAAAAAAUCCAAGAACACAAUUCAUUUUCACCACCUCUGGUGUUCAGAGGGGGCUUUUAAAAAAGCGUGUAUGCUGGGAUACCCAUUAAAACCAUUUUCUAGAAGGCUACCAUGAGCUGCACUUUUUGGGGUGGGAAAGGUGAAUGCCAGUGGGGAUGCGGGGGGAUGAGGGUAGGAGGGACUUAUAGAAGGGGAUUUGUGGCUGUGGGGGAGAAGGUUCUACAGCAUAAGCCUUAUCCUGCCAGCCAAGGGGAUUUAUUCUAAGAGAAGUGCAUGUGAAGAAUGGUUGCCACUGUUAUUAGAUUGACAAGAUGUUAAUUUCUCUGUAGGUUGUAACUUUAAAAAUAAAUGAAAUUAUUUAAGGGUUAUGCUGCACUAGUAUUCCUUAGAGGAAACAGUUCUUUAAAGUUAGGAAAGGGAGUAGGCAGGCAUGUGUUGGCAAAGGCUGUUAAUAGUAGUUAAGUGUUAAGACUGCUUUUCUUUAACGUUUUCAUGGUAAUGCAUAUUUAGAGCACUGUAUUUUUGUCUUGUUAAGAAAAUUUAGCAUUUCUAAAAGAAAAAAGCAACCCUCUUUCAAACUGUUAAUUCUGUCACAGCCUGUAUAUUUUAGUCAUUUGUAAAUCUCUUCAUACAAUAGUGACUUCUUUUUUGACUGAUACAGUAUCUUAAUUACAAGGUUAUUUUGUACUUGUCUUAAUACACUAAGUGUAAUAAAAACGGCUUGAGAAAAGUUUCUCCUUUCUGUGACUUCAAAUAAGAACUCCCAGUAUUGCCUAAAUCUUCUAGGCAACCCUUUUUCCAUAAGGAAGAGCAUGGAGUGCUGUGGUCACCAGUAAUCAUUUUCAAUUAAUUAAGGUCAUGAACAGUAAUAAUUUAAGCCUUGUUUACCAAGGUUUGAAUUCUACUUUUGCUGUUGCUAAAGCUGUGGGCAAUGAGGAGACACAGUGGCAGAUAAAGACGAGGUGGUGACGCUGGAGGAGUGGGCCUCGGCUGCACACUGCAGUCUCGAAGCUUAAGUGUUGCUGUCAGUCAGUUCUCAUCCCCAGAGAAUUAUUUAAUUAAUUAACUGGGGGGGGUACACUGGGGCAUUAGACUUUUAAAAGCUCCCCGAGGGAAUUCAAAUGUGCAUUCAGAGUUGAGAAUCAGAUGGAUUCUUUCUUUUGUGGAAAUGUUUUAUAAUAUUGGACUCUUAAUCCGCAUUUCAUUAUUAAAGCAUGCUGUGGAGAAAAA